ACCUUACGUGUCUUUUUUCUUUUGGGAAAGAAUCUCGCCCUGUCGCCCAGGCUGCAGUGCAGUAGCACAAUCUCGGCUCACUGCAACCUCCGCCUCCCGGGUUCAAGCGAUUCUCCUGCCUCAGCCUCCCAAGUAGCUGGGACUACAGGCGUGUGCCACCUCGCCCGGCUAAUUUUUUGUAUUUUUGGUAGAGACAGGGGUUUCACCGUGUUAGCCAGGAUGGUCUCGAUUUCCUGACCUCGUGAUCCACCCGCCUCGGCCUCCCAAAGUGCUGGGAUUACAGCCACCGCGCCCGGCCACCUUACAUGUCUUUAAUAAUACUCCUAUAAAGCAAUUUGGGAAUGAACAAAAAUCUUUAUAAAAAUUUGAAAGUGAUUCUAGACAAAAAUUCCCAAGCAUUGGAUCACUAAUGGUUUUUGAAGAAUGGCAAUUAAUGUAGAUUAGAUAGAGUUGGUGAAAGGGGGCUAAACAUAUUUAGGUUUCUGUUGGGUUACUUUGGAUUUUUGAAUGUACCUAUAAAUUACAGAUGGUUCCCCAAAGCCUCCAAGACUCAAUGGUAAUAAAUAGAAUGACUUAGGUUAUACAGUAUUGUAUUAUGCAUUCAUAAAGCUUCUGGAUUAUCUAGAAGUGUUUGCUAUUUACAAUGUGAAGUUUGCGAAGUGCCGCGUGGAUUUUUAUGUGAAACAAGCAUUUCUGUUACGGUUCAGAAAGGUAUGAAACACCAAAGAGAGCGCUGAAAAUGGACUCACUGUCAUCUUCCUUCAGUUCUCCUAAUGAUCCAGAUGGACAGAAUGAUAUCUUUUGGGAUCAGAAUUCUCCAUUGACAAAGCAGUUAGGUAAAGGAAGAAAAAAACAGAUUUACACCACAGAUAGUGAUGAGAUUUCACAUAUUGUUAAUCGUAUUGCUCCUCAGGAUGAAAAACCAACAACAAAUUCUAUGCUGGACAUGUGGAUUGGUGAAACUGCUAUUCCUUGUACUCCCAGUGUAGCAAAAGGAAAAUCAAGAGCAAAAAUCAGCUGCACAAAGUUAAAAACACAAAGUCAAGAAGAAGAACUUAUGAAACUGGCUAAACAAUUUGAUAAAAAUAUGGAAGAGCUAGAUGUGAUUCAAGAGCAAAACAAGAGGAAUUAUGAUUUUACCCAGAUGAUUUCAGAAACAGAGAUUUUAAGUAAUUAUAAAGAUAAUAUACAGAUGUGGUCAUUACAUAAUAUAGUUCCCGAAAUAGAUAAUGCUACAAAAAAGCCAAUCAAAGGAAACACCAAGAUAUCUGUGGCAAAUAAUCAAAAUAGCAGUCAGAAGCCAUUUGACCAAAUUGCUGAAGCAGCCUUUAAUGCUAUUUUUGAUGGUUCUACUCAGAAAUGUAGCGGACAGUUAAGCCAAGAACUGCCAGAGGCUUUUUGGAGCACCAGUAAUACUACCUUUGUAAAGACAAAUGCUUUGAAAGAGGAGAAAAUCAUUACUAAUGAAACUCUGGUCAUUGAAAAACUGUCAAAUAAAACCCCACGAUCACUUUCUUCUCAAGUAGAUACACCCAUAAUGACAAAAUCAUGUGUGACUUCCUGUACUAAGGAGCCAGAAACUUCUAAUAAGUACAUUGAUGCAUUUACUACAAGUGAUUUUGAGGAUGAUUGGGAAAACUUACUAGGUAGUGAACCUUUUGCUAUGCAAAAUAUCGACAUGCCUGAACUCUUUCCUUCUAAAACAGCCCAUGUUACUGAUCAAAAGGAAAUUUGUACCUUUAAUAGUAAAACUGUUAAAAAUACGUCAAGAGCAAAUACAAGUCCAGAUGCCAGGUUAGGAGAUUCAAAAGUAUUACAAGAUCUUUCUUCAAAGACAUAUGACAGAGAAUUAAUAGAUGCAGAAUAUAGAUUUUCACCAAAUUCAAAUAAAUCAAACAAAUUAUCCACUGGAAAUAAAAUGAAAUUUGAGAACUCUUCCAAUAAAAUUGUUAUUCAAGACGAAAUUCAAAAUUGUAUAGUUACAUCUAAUCUGACAAAAAUAAAGGAAGAUAUUCUUACUAACUCUACUGAAGCUUCUGAAAGGAAGUCAGCUUUGAACACAAGGUAUUCUAAUGAACAGAAAAAUAAGUGCAUUUUAAAUCAGUCUAUUAAAGCCCCUGUUAAUACUGAUCUUUUUGGCUCUGCAAAUCUAGGCAGUAAAACCAGUGUUAGUAACCCAAAUCAGACUAGUGCAUCAAAAGUAGGUUCUUUCUUUGAUGAUUGGAAUGAUCCCUCAUUUGCCAAUGAAAUUAUUAAAGCAUGUCAUCAAUUAGAUAAUACCUGGGAAGCAGAUGAUGUAGAUGAUGAUUUGUUGUACCAAGCAUGUGAUGAUAUUGAAAGACUAACUCAGCAACAAGACAUUAGAAAGGACAGUAAGACAUCAGAAAGUAUAUGUGAGAUCAAUAAUAAUUCCGAACAUGGAGCCAAACUAACUCAGCAACAAGACAUUAGAAAGGACAGUAAGACAUCAGAAAGUAUAUGUGAGAUCAAUAAUAAUUCCGAACAUGGAGCCAAAAACAUGUUUGCUAUAUCUAAACAAGGAAGUAAUUUGGUACAAUCAAAGCAUUUGAAUCCAGGCAGCAUUUCAGUGCAGACAUCUUUGACAAAUAGCUCACAAAUAGAUAAGCCAAUGAAGAUGGAGAAAGGGGAAAUGUAUGGAAAUUCUCCAAGAUUUUUAGGUGCCACAAAUUUGACUAUGUAUUCUAAGAUCUCAAACUGUCAGAUAAAUAAUCUGCAUGUGUCUUAUACUAACACUGAUGUUCCAAUACAAGUGAAUAGUUCCAAAUUGGUUCUUCCAGGAAGUUCAAGUUUGAAUGUAACUUCAGAUCAUAUGAAUACAGAAAUUACUACUUAUAAGAAGAAAUUGAGUACUAAUCAGCCAUGCCAUAAGACUGUAACAGAUGAAGCUCAGAGCAACCUUAACACAACAGUUGGAUUUUCAAAGUUUACAUUUACAAGGAUGAAAAAUUCUCAGAUUCUUUCUCAGUUUAAUCAAAAUUGUAUAACUGGAAGUAUGUCUGAUACCAAAAUUACACAGGGUGUGGAGAAAAAGAAAGGUGUCAACCCAUUACUGGAGGAAGCUGUUGGACAGCAAUCUUUGGUGAAACUUUCUGAAUCUUUGAAACAAUCUUCAAAAGAGGAAGAAGAGAAAAAUAGAAAGUGUUCUCCUGAAGAAAUUCAGAGAAAAAGACAAGAAGCACUGGUUCGGAGAAUGGCUAAAGCACGAGCCUCAUCUGUAAAUGCAGCUCCCACUUCAUUUCUUUAAUGAAAUAUUAGUUGGAAGACUUCACGAAGACUGCUGAUAACUAUCUGUGAUUGAUAGGAAAUUUUUUUUCUUGAUUUCUCUGUGAGAAAUGUAAUGCUGACUUUUAUAAAGCCUGGACUUCUACUUUAUUUAAUAAAUCAAUGUUUGCAAUGGUAAAUGAAACAUUUCCUUGGACAUGUAUUUGAAAGUCAUUAAAUACAAAAGUUUUGGAAAUUCAGGAAAGUUAGCAAUUAUGUACGGAUAUUAUACAGAGGAAAGUAGUUAUAUUUUUAAAUGCUAUUAUUGCAGAGGAUCAUCAAAAAAGAGGUAAUCUACGUUAUUUCCUAUUCUAAUGUCUUUUCCUAAUAAAAAACUUCAACUUUCUAAGUUAGUAGAGACUGUUUUUGUAGUUUUACUUUCAUUAACUGUUGCUUAAGGUUUUUAUACACUUCCAGAUUUUAAUUAAUACUUUCAUAUUUCUAGGAACAUGGUUGAUAUGAAAUAAAGGACUUUUUAUUUGUAAGGAAAUUAUGUUCAGUUCUUAGAAGUGGAUUUGAAUUUUAAUAAUUCUAAAAUGUGACACAUUUUGGAAACUUUCCACCAUAUUUAGGAAAACUUUGAUUUUAGAAGUCUAACAUAGAGGAAAAGAAGUAGUGGAUUGUCUACAAAAGUAAUGUGGCAUCAUUAACAUUUAGAACUGGCAGAAACUUCAUAUGUCAUCUGGUCCAGCUUCCUUAUUGUAUCGGUGAGAAAAAGUAAUACUGUUUUCAAAGUCAUAGGCAAGUUAAUGCUGUGCUACAAUUAGAAUGAUUUAUUUGGACACCUAAACAAUUAUACUAUUUGUUUCAAAGUAUCAGUACAUAAAAUAACUUGAGGGAGUAUUAUUUUCUAGUAUAAAACAAAAGAUGUAAUUAAAAGCACAAUAAGGACUGUUUGAUAAUAAUGCUCAUUGUUCCUUAUUUUGCUUUAAAGAAUUAGUCUUUCCAGGAUAUAAAAAUGAGAAUCUUUUUUCUUUUCAGUUUUUCUGUAACUGUAAUUUUCCCCUCAAUUAAUUUACUUAGUUGACUCAUCUUUUCUUCUCUAUUACUGUUUUGUUUUUUUCUUUUUUUGCCAUUUUGCCUAUUUGGAAUUUGCUAAACCAGUAAUAGAAGUCCAACUAGAGGGCGUAAGGCAGGGAGGAUGCUUUAUUCCUCUUAAAUGGUUUUAGGAGAUCUAGAGAAAGUUAGAGAUAUGAAACACCUGUCAUGGUGUGGCAUUUAUCACUAUCAAGUGUCUCAAAGCUGUGAUAAUAUGGUAGUUACUGCCCUAUAGCUAUACAGAUACUCCUCAACUUACCGUGUAGUUACAUCCCAAUAAACCCAUCAUGAGUUGAAAAUACCUUAAGUUAAAAAUGCAUUUACUACACUUAAUCUACCAGACAACAUAGCUUAGCUUAGCCUACCUUAAACAUGCUCAAAUCACUUAUAUUAGCCUAGAGUUGGGCACAUCAUCUGGCAAUACGGCACACUGUAGAGUAUCAGUUGAGCUGAUGCCCAGCAUCGUGAGAAUGUUGUACCACAUAUCUCUAGCCUGGGAAAGAAUCAAACUUUAAAGUAUGGUUUCUAUUGGACGCAUAUCACUUUUGCAUCACGUUAGAGUUGAAAAAUUGUAAGUCAACCAUUUUAAGUUGGAGACUGUACAUCAAAAAUGGUAUUUUCAUAUCUACAGUGGAGUACUGGAGUUUAGCUAACCUAUAUUAUUUUUCCAGGAAUAUAUAAUAACCUAGAUAAAUGCAAGUAGUUUCUAUGUACAAAAAUAAAGAGCUGAGAAUCUUUUACUAAAAGUGGCUUCACUGUGUUCUGACUAUGCUUUGGAUAUCUCUGUCCUUGCUUAAGCUCCUCCCUGCUUACUGCUUGCUUUUUUAAGAGUACUUUUAGCCUAUUCUGUUCAUUCAUUUAGACUCAGCCUAAUAAGUCUGUUUGAACCUCGUACCUAACCAUCUUCACUGGAAUUGAUUGCUUCUCUCUGAUCAUAAUGGUACUAAUUAUUGUGUCUUUCAUUGAGCAAUACUAUAAUGCCUUUAUGUGUUGUUU